GCAUUCCCUUGGGCAGAGAUGGGAGAUGGCGCCGGUGUUGCCCCUGGUGCUGCCCCUGCAGCCCCGCAUCCGCCUGGCACAAGGGCUCUGGCUCCUCUCCUGGCUGCUGGCGCUGGCUGGUGGCGUCAUCCUCCUCUGUAGUGGGCACCUCCUGGUCCAGCUAAGGCACCUUGGCACCUUCCUGGCUCCCUCCUGUCAGUUCCCUGUCCUGCCCCAGGCUGCCCUGGCAGCGGGCGCGGUGGCUCUGGGCACAGGACUAGUGGGUGUAGGAGCCAGCCGGGCAAGUCUGAAUGCAGCUCUAUACCCUCCCUGGCGAGGGGUCCUGGGCCCGCUGCUGGUGGCUGGCACGGCUGGUGGGGGGGGGCUCCUGGUCGUCGGCCUCGGGCUAGCCCUGGCUUUGCCUGGGAGUCUGGAUGAGGCGCUGGAGGAGGGCCUGGUGACUGCCUUGGCUCACUACAAGGACACAGAGGUGCCUGGGCACUGUCAGGCCAAAAGGCUGGUGGAUGAGCUGCAACUGAGGUACCACUGCUGCGGGCGCCACGGGUACAAGGAUUGGUUUGGGGUCCAGUGGGUCAGCAGCCGUUACCUGGAUCCCGGUGACCGGGAUGUGGCUGACCGGAUCCAGAGCAAUGUAGAAGGCCUAUACCUGACUGAUGGGGUCCCUUUCUCCUGUUGCAACCCCCACUCACCCCGGCCUUGCCUGCAAAACCGUCUUUCAGACUCCUACGCCCACCCCCUGUUCGAUCCCCGACAACCCAACCAAAACCUCUGGGCCCAAGGGUGCCAUGAGGUGCUGCUGGAGCACUUGCAGGACUUGGCAGGCACACUGGGUAGCAUGCUGGCUGUCACCUUCCUACUGCAGGCUCUGGUGCUCCUUGGCCUGCGGUACCUGCAAACAGCACUGGAGGGGCUUGGAGGGGUCAUUGAUGCGGGAGGAGAGACCCAGGGCUAUCUCUUUCCCAGUGGGCUGAAAGAUAUGCUGAAAACAGCAUGGCUACAGGGAGGGGUUGCCUGCAGGCCAGCACCUGAGGAGGCCCCACCAGGAGAAGCACCUCCCAAGGAGGAUCUAUCUGAGGCCUAGAGGCCUGGAGCUUGGGGUGAGGAAGAGGGAGGGAUGGACAAGUCUGAAAACCUCACAACUCCUUACCAAGGCUCCAGGUUGGGGGGAUCGUAGGAUUAGAGGGGCUAAGGAUAGUCAGCGAGCUGGACUGGGGUAAGAAAGAAAACCAGAUGUCCUAGGGCCUAGCCCUUGUAGUCAGAACCACCAGGGAACAGCAAAGAACAGAGUGAUGGGAAAGUGACAUGAGAAGGCCUGGAGGCUGAUUCUGAUAUAGACUCAAUAAAGUUUUUGGAUGGAA